AGUGAGCAUUCUCAGCACAUUGCCUCAACAGCUUCAAGGUGAGCCAGCUCAAGACUUUGCUCUCCACCAGGCAGAAGAUGACAGACUGUGAAUUUGGAUAUAUUUACAGGCUGGCUCAGGACUAUCUGCAGUGCGUCCUACAGAUACCACAACCUGGAUCAGGUCCAAGCAAAACGUCCAGAGUGCUACAAAAUGUUGCGUUCUCAGUCCAAAAAGAAGUGGAAAAGAAUCUGAAGUCAUGCUUGGACAAUGUUAAUGUUGUGUCCGUAGACACUGCCAGAACACUAUUCAACCAAGUGAUGGAAAAGGAGUUUGAAGACGGCAUCAUUAACUGGGGAAGAAUUGUAACCAUAUUUGCAUUUGAAGGUAUUCUCAUCAAGAAACUUCUACGACAGCAAAUUGCCCCGGAUGUGGAUACCUAUAAGGAGAUUUCAUAUUUUGUUGCGGAGUUCAUAAUGAAUAACACAGGAGAAUGGAUAAGGCAAAACGGAGGCUGGGGGAAAUGGCACAAUCACACACCUAUGCUGGUAGAGUCAGUGGCCCACAAGAAGAGGAAAAUGGCUUUGUAAAGAAGUUUGAACCUAAAUCUGGCUGGAUGACUUUUCUAGAAGUUACAGGAAAGAUCUGUGAAAUGCUAUCUCUCCUGAAGCAAUACUGUUGACCAGAAAGGACACUCCAUAUUGUGAAACCGGCCUAAUUUUUCUGACUGAUAUGGAAACGAUUGCCAACACAUACUUCUACUUUUAAAUAAACAACUUUGAUGAUGUAACUUGACCUUCCAGAGUUAUGGAAAUUUUGUCCCCAUGUAAUGAAUAAAUUGUAUGUAUUUUUCUCUA